CAAUCCACCCACCUCAGCCUCCCAAAGUGCUGGGAUUACAGGCGUGAGUCACCGCGCCCGGCCUAACUAAUUUUAAGUAGCUAAAGAAGCUUCCUUCUGUCAUCAUUUUUGGACAGUAAUUUCAUGAUUCAGAAUACACUGUAGUGUUGGUAUCAGGUCAAUGCUAAAACUUACUUUUCCUUUUUGAGAACUUGAUGCUUACCUCCCCUCUAGAACUAGGUCCUAGGCUUCUUACAUCCUUCAGACAAGCGAGUCUGAAAUAAAGCAGAGUUGGUUUCUCUGAAACCAACUGCACUAACAGAAUGUGCAUUUCAUAUUCUGGCUACAGCAGGCUCUUCUAUUUUAGGAGCCUAAAGCUGAAGCUGCUCCAAGAUGGAGAAUUUCCUUCUCUCUUUCACCCCCGAUGCAAUUAGAAGUUUCUAUCCAUUUAUAGAUUAUUUCUAGAGCUAGAGUAGCAGCCUCUAUUUUUGUGCAAAGUAUUGCAUUUAUGCACAAUAGCCGCCGAGUUGAGCCCUCCAAAUGGUCUUGCUGAAGAUAACUUGAUCGUUGAUGUAUCACAUCAUCUAGAAAGGUGCAGGAGAUCAUGAAAAACAAGCCUGUAGUGGAGCAAGGGCAGCAGGUGCUCUUCUCUCUUUAUGGCUCGAGAUGGCCCCAGGAGGCCUCCUCUACGGGUAGGGCUGGAAAGGGAAGGGGGCAUCUUCUGAAGCUUUUGCUUGGAAACUGUAUCUUUCCAGCCAAUUGUCACCUCGUGUUCUUUGUAGCAUAUCUGGGAGGAUUUCAAUCUAAAACGGAGGCAGCAGUAGAAUGAAGGUCUCCCAUCAAUCUUCCAACUGGUGAUACGUGAAGCAGCCAUUUACUGACCCUUGAAUAUCACUCUUGCACCAGGGCUGAAGGAAGGCUCUGACAGAUAGAAGUAUUAAAGCUGAAAACAUUGAUACAAAGUAAUAUUGAUAUCUUUCAGAUAAAGUGAAAUAGCAAAAACAGAAUUCCUCCUCAGGGAGUAUAUGAAAUAUGGUUUUUUUCUGCUGCAAAUGUCUCCAAAACAUUGGCAAAUCCAGCAAGCACUAAAAAGAGCACAGGCAUCAAAAAGUAAAGCAAAUAUCAUCCUUCCAAAAAUAUUAGCAAAAUUAUCAUUACAUUCAAGUAACAAGGAAGGCAUCCUUGAGGAGUCCGGGAGGACAGCUGUCCUUUCAGAAGAUGCUUCUCAGGGAAGAGACAGCCAAGGAAAGCCAAGCAGAAGCCUGACUCGCACUCCAGAGAAAAAGAAAUCAAACCUGGCUGAAAGUUUCGGUUCAGAAGACAGUUUGGAAUUCCUUUUAGAUGAUGAAAUGGACGUUGAUUUGGAGCCAGCACUUUAUUUCAAGGAACCAGAGGAGUUACUUCAAGUCCUCAGAGAGCUGGAAGAGCAGAAUCUUACUUUGUUUCAAUAUUCCCAAGAUGUAGAUGAAAAUCUUGAAGAGGUAAACAAAAGAGAAAAAGUUAUACAGGAUAAAACAAAUAGCAACAUAGAGUUUCUUUUGGAGCAAGAAAAAAUGCUUAAAGCUAACUGUGUGAGAGAAGAAGAGAAAGCAGCAGAAUUGCAAUUAAAGUCCAAGCUCUUUAGCUUUGGAGAAUUUAAUUCAGAUGCUCAGGAAAUACUGAUAGACUCACUUAGUAAAAAGAUUACUCAAGUAUACAAAGUCUGCAUUGGAGAUGCUGAGGAUGACGGCCUCAACCCAAUUCAAAAGCUGGUAAAAGUAGAAUCUCGCCUGGUAGAACUGUGUGACCUCAUCGAAUCCAUUCCCAAAGAAAAUGUGGAGGCAAUUGAGAGGAUGAAACAGAAAGAAUGGCGGCAAAAGUUUCGUGAUGAGAAAAUGAAAGAAAAACAAAGACACCAACAGGAAAGGCUAAAAGCUGCUCUGGAAAAAGCAGUAGCACAACCAAAGAAAAAGUUGGGAAGACGACUUGUCUUUCAUUCAAAACCUCCAUCUGGUAACAAACAGCAGCUACCUUUAGUCAAUGAAACAAAAACAAAAUCACAAGAGGAAGAAUAUUUUUUUACUUGAAUAAAAGCAGUAAGACAUUUUAUUACCA